GUCCUACCCCGUGAUAUUAAAGCAAGAUGGCCGCGCCCUGCAGAUUGUCUCUUGUUGCGUAAGUUUUUUUGACCGUCACUCGUGUCAGCUUCAAAGUCAGAUAGAUUUUUCUCCCAGCAUGUUCUACUUCCGAGGCUGUGGCCGUUGGGUCGCGGUUUCCUUCACCAAGCAGCAAUUUCCGUUGGCACGGUUGAGCAGUGACAGCGCGGCGCCCCGGACUCCGCACUUCGACGUGAUAGUCAUUGGUGGAGGACAUGCCGGGACUGAGGCAGCCACCGCCGCCGCUCGGUGCGGCUCUCGGACUCUGCUCCUCACUCACCGCGUGGACACGAUCGGUCAGAUGUCAUGUAAUCCUUCCUUUGGUGGCAUCGGAAAGGGACAUUUAAUGAGGGAAGUAGAUGCCUUGGAUGGCCUGUGUUCUCGCAUCUGUGACCAGUCUGGUGUACAUUAUAAAGUAUUAAACCGGCGUAAGGGACCAGCUGUGUGGGGUCUGAGAGCUCAGAUUGAUAGGAAACUCUAUAAACAGAACAUGCAGAAAGAAAUCUUGAAUACACCACUGCUUACUGUUCAGGAGGGAGCUGUAGAAGAUCUUAUUCUUACAGAACCAGAGCCUGAACACACUGGGAAAUGCCGUGUCAGUGGGGUUGUUUUGGUGGAUGGAAGCACAGUAUAUGCAGAGAGUGUGAUUCUGACUACUGGGACAUUUCUGAGAGGCAUGAUUGUAAUUGGAUUGGAGACGCAUCCAGCAGGACGUUUAGGGGAUCAGCCUUCUAUAGGAUUGGCUCAGACACUGGAGAAGUUAGGGUUUGUGGUGGGAAGGUUGAAGACUGGGACUCCACCCCGAAUUGCCAAAGAGUCCAUUAAUUUCAGUAUUCUAAACAAGCAUAUACCGGACAAUCCAUCCAUACCAUUCAGCUUUACCAAUGAGACAGUAUGGAUUAAGCCAGAAGAUCAGCUGCCAUGUUACUUGACUCACACCAACCCUAGAGUGGAUGAGAUUGUCCUUAAGAACCUUCACCUUAAUAGUCAUGUUAAAGAAACGACAAGAGGACCUCGAUACUGUCCCUCCAUUGAAUCAAAAGUUUUGCGUUUUCCAAACCGUCUACAUCAGGUUUGGUUGGAACCUGAAGGAAUGGAUUCUGACCUUAUCUACCCACAGGGGUUAUCUAUGACGCUACCAGCUGAGUUACAAGAGAAAAUGAUCACAUGCAUCAGAGGCUUGGAGAAAGCUAAAGUGAUUCAGCCAGGCUACGGUGUUCAGUAUGAUUACUUAGAUCCCCGUCAGAUCACCCCUUCCUUGGAGACUCAUUUGGUUCAACGACUCUUCUUUGCUGGACAGAUCAAUGGCACCACUGGUUAUGAGGAAGCUGCAGCUCAAACAGAGUGUUGCUCUGUUGCCAGGCUGGAGUGCAGUGAUAUGAUCUCCCAGCUUCAAGCGAUCCUCCUGCCUCAGCCCUCCCUAGUAGCUGGGACUGCAGGCAUGCACCACAACACCCAGGGUGUGAUAGCCGGAAUCAACGCCAGUCUUCGGGUCAGUCGCAAGCCUCCCUUUGUGGUUAGCCGAACAGAAGGUUACAUAGGAGUCUUGAUUGAUGACCUCACUACUCUGGGCACCAGUGAACCAUACCGCAUGUUUACCAGCCGAGUAGAGUUCCGUUUGUCACUGCGCCCUGAUAAUGCUGACAGCCGGCUCACACUGCGAGGGUAUAAAGACGCUGGCUGUGUGUCCCAACAACGAUAUGAAAGAGCUUGUUGGAUGAAGUCUUCUUUAGAAGAAGGCAUUUCUGUGUUGAAAUCUAUUGAGUUUUUGAGCUCUAAAUGGAAAAAAUUAAUCCCAGAGGCUUCUAUAAGUACUAGUAGAAGUCUGCCUGUCAGAGCUCUCGAUGUUCUGAAGUAUGAGGAAGUUGACAUGGAUUCAUUAGCCAAGGCUGUUCCAGAGCCCUUGAAGAAGUAUACUAAAUGUAGAGAGCUGGCUGAAAGACUGAAAAUAGAAGCCACUUAUGAAUCAGUGUUGUUCCAUCAACUACAAGAAAUAAAGGGAGUUCAGCAAGAUGAAGCUCUCCAACUGCCAAAAGACCUAGAUUAUUUGACUAUCAGGGAUGUGUCUUUGUCCCAUGAAGUUCGAGAGAAACUACAUUUUAGUCGUCCACAGACGAUCGGGGCUGCUAGUCGCAUACCCGGAGUAACACCUGCCGCCAUCAUCAAUCUGCUGAGAUUUGUGAAGACCACUCAACGAAGACAGUCGGCUAUGAAUGAAUCAUCCAAGACUGAUCAAUACUUAUGUGAUGCAGACAGACUUCAAGAGAGAGAGUUAUAGCUUUCAAUUCAUAAAAGAUUUUUAAAGAGCAUAUAAAUAAUUUGAUCAAUACAACAGUAUAGAUAAAAGAAUUAUUUAGCACAUGUUAAAAUAGCUUUAUUAGGUUACUAUGGGUUUGCCAUUAAUUUCUGAGUGGGACAGAAAUUAUAAUUGUGCUUUUUCGUGUAUAUGAAAAAACUAGUCGUAAACAAUUUGUACUCUUUCUUUAAGGAGCUGUAAUACAAAUAACUUUGUGCAGUGUUCAUCAAAGAGAGAGACAGUGAACCUAAAACUGAACCUGGAAUAAAACUCAACAUGCAGAUUUGCCUACUCAUAGGGACUUUGCCUAUUAAGUCUACCAAAUUAAAAGUCUUAUCAUUCAGCGUGUUUUGAGAGUUAAUAAUCUUUUGCUUGGUUAUACUAGGCUAGGAAGCAAUAUCAAAGCCCUUAAAUUCUCAAGACUAAAGACUUGAGAUUAUAUAAAAUUAUCCAGAAUCAUUCAGCUAAUACUAUUGGAAUAUAGUAUGUAGGGUGAAAGUUGACAGAAAUCUGUACUUCUUCAGGAAAUCCUCACUGGUAAUUGUUUUGAACAUUAAUGAAAGCCCUAUAAAAUAGAAAGAUUGGAAAUCACCAUUGUUUCCUAUUAUCCACAGUGUGGAUGGAUACUUAUUUGGUGACCUAGUUAUGGGAGAAUUGAGUAACGUUAGUUAUUUUAUAUCAUACCAUAAAAAUAUUUUCUUAAGAAAUUGUCAUGGCCAUCAUUUCUUAAUAAUGAAGACAGGUCCAUAGUAACUGGUGAGUGGUGUUUCCCUGUUUUUAAGUCAGAAUGACAGAAAAAACAGAAUAGUGGUAGUACCCCUCUUCCUCUCCAGUACUUCAAUGGUAUGUCUUCACAGGGGUUAGAGUGGGAUAAUCAGCUGGGCCUUUUGACUCAGAUACCUCAGAUACCUCAACCAUUCUAAAUAGACUAAGGGAUGAAUACAGCCAAAUGGGCCAGACAGCCCUGCUUGUCUCUGGAAUUCCAACCCAGAUCUCUGGUGUCAGCCUAGGGAGAAGCUCCCGUGUCACCUUCGGGCCAAAGCAGGUACUCAGGAGAGUUCUAAGGGCCCCAAAGUCACUUUGGCUACAGAUGUGUAUGUUAAGCCUGAUUAUGGGUGUGAGGCAACCAAGUAUCUUGUUACUAUAAUUGCAUAUGGCCACUUGGAGGUAGCUUAGUUUUCUUGGGUUUAUUUUAUCUAAUUUUAGUCUUUCCAGAAAGCAGUAAGAUUAGUAGCAAGUAAAAAGUAUUUGUAGUGCUGGAUAAUUUAGGAAUGAUGAAUAUUUUUUAAUACUUGAUUCAGUGAUUUCAAAAGGUCGUAACUUUUAGUCAUAGCUACUCCUGGGCAAAAUUCUUCUUACAGAGACAAUAUUAAUUACAAUACCACAUUGUGUAUAUAUUUUGAAAAGAGGCUGGUUGCAGCAGCUCACGCCUGUAAUCCCAGCACUUUGGGAGGCUGAGGCGGGUGGAUAACCUGAAGUCAGGAGUUCAAGACCAGCCUGGCCAACAUGGCAAAACCCCAUCUCCACUAAAAAUACCAAAAUUAGCCAGGCGUGGUGGAGCAAGCCUGUAGUCCCAGCUACUCAGGAGGCUGAGGCAGGAGAAUCGCUUGAACCCAGGAGGCAGAGGUUGCAGUGAGCUGAGAUUGUGCCACUGCACUCCAGCCUGGGCGACAGAGUGAGACUGUUUCAAAAAAAAGAAAAAGAAAAGAAGGUAUUUUGUGUUUUUGUGCUACCCGUUCAGCAAAAUAAUGAAAUUCAUUGUUUCUAAACUUUUUUUUCUGAUUAAAUACAAGAGUAAAAAAAGUGAAUGGAGUGCCUUUUGAAUAGAAUAUAACAAAAAUUUAUCUUAAAGAAACGGGAAGUAACCUGGCACAGUGGCUCACGCCUGUAAUCCCAGCACUUUGGGAGGCUGAGGCAGGUGGAUCACGAGGUCAGGAGAUCGAGACCAUCCUGCCCAACAUGGUGAAACCCCAUCUCUACUAAAAAUACAAAAAUUAGCUAGGUGUGUUGGCACGUGCCUGUAGUCCCAACUACUCAGGAGGCUGAGGCAAGAGAAUCACUUGAACUCAGGAGGCAGAGGUUGCAGUGAGCCAAGAUCAUGCCACUGCACUCCAGCCUGGCAACAGAGUGAGACUCUGUCUCAAAAAAAAAAAAAGAAACAGGAAGUUCAAAUAUUUUGGGAGGUUCUUGACAGCUACAAUUUGGGGCUAGUGACACUAUACACAUAUAAAGAAACUUUAAAGUUUCUUAGUAAUGAAGGUUUGUAAUGCUAUUCCAUUACAAUAGUAACUGUCUCACUGAAAAAUGUUUCAUGGAAAAUACAUAUUUUAGAUUCUAUGAUUUGCUUUAGGAUGUGAACUUCUUUAUUUUUUAGAGACAGGGUCUCACUCUGUUGCCCAGGCUGUAGUGCAGUGGUACAAUCAUAGCUCACUGCAGCCUUGAUCUCCUGGGCUCAAGUGAUCCUUAUGCCUCAGCCUCCCAAGUGGCUGGGACUACAGGCACAUGCCACCAUGCCUGGCUAAGUUUUAAAAAAAUUUUUUGUAGGAAUGAAGUCUCACUAUGUUGCCCAGGCUGGUCUUGAACUUCUGGCCUCAAAUGAUCCUCUUGCCUUGGCCUCCCAAAGUGCUCAGAUUACAGGCAUGAGCCACCACACGUGGCCUGAAACCUCUUUAAAUCCACAAUGUUUGUAUGUUAACUUAAACAAAAUUACAUCACUUAAUAUGUCAAAACAGCCUACCCUCUGGUGCUGCUAUGCAGAAGUACUACAGAAUAUGAUGCCCUAGGAAGAAAUCAGCUAAAAAUGUAACCUUACUCAAUGUAGUUACUUCAUAGAAAUCCCAUCACUGACAAUAAUCAGCUGCCAACGAAAGCUGGCCAUACUUGUGACUUCCUCUAUUCACCACAGACCAGACUGCCUACCAGUUGAAAAAGCCAGGUAUUUUUUCAAUUCAAUUCAACAGGAACACCAAAAAAUAAGAAAUGACUAAGAAACACUAAGCAUUUGUAAAAUUACUGGGGGAGGAAGGAUGAAGAUACGAACCUAUGCUAAAUUAAACGAUUAUGGCCUUGAAAAUGAAGUUCCUUUAUAGCCAAGAGCUUAAAUUUUGUUACUGAUGGUUUUAAAAGUAUUUUGUCAUUUUUUAGUUUCAACCUAGAUUGGAAUAGCCAUGGCUUUUCUACUUCAGAAAUUUCAACUCCUAGAAGAAUGCCCUGUCCAGAAGAAGUGGUCAGGAGUAUCAGGAAAGCCACCAGCAGAGACUAGGGGUUUAUUCUGAUCUGGAAGAGCCACUUAACACUGGAAUGCACACAGUGAAAAUUAAUUGUUCCUCUUACACUCCCUCUCCACAAUACUUCUAUUAUUACACUUACUUCGUUCUACCUUAAUGUUUUUAUUUAGAGACAAGAUCUCACUCUGCCACCCUGGCUGGAGUGCAGUGGCAUGAUUACAGCUCACUGCAGCCUCAACCUCCCUGGCUCUAGCUAUUCUCCCAUCUCAGCCCUCCAAGUAGCUGGGACUACAGGUGUGCACCACCAUGCACGGCUAAUUUUUAAGUUUUUGUAGAUAUGGGGUCUUACUAUGUUGCCCAGGCUGGUCUCAAAGUCCUGGGCUCAAUUAAUCCUCCCUCUUCAGCCUCCUGUGUAGGUGAUAGUACAGGCAUGAGCCACCAUGUGCCUGGCCCUACCUUAAUGUUAAUAUCUGUCUACCUUAAGAAGAUAUAAGCCUUGUAAAUAUAAGCAAUAUCACAGUUGUAGAUACUCGUGCUUUUUAAAUAGAUUAAUGAAUACUACUAAAGGCAAGAAAUGGUAUUACUAAAACUCAAGUGAAUAAUUAAAUGAGAUCAAAAUAUUUGUGACAGGCCAGGCACGGUGGCUUACGCCUGUAAUCCCAGCACUUUGGGAGGCCAGGCGGAUCACUUGAGCUCAGCAGUUCAAGACCAGCCUGGGCAACAUGGCGAAACUCCGUCUUUACCAAAAAUACAAAAAUAAGCCAAGCAUGGUGGCACGUACCUGUUGUUCCAGCAACUUGGGGGCUGAGGCAGGAGAAUCACUUGAGCCGGGGAGUUUGAGGCUGCAGUGAGUUGAUAGCAUGCCACCACACUCCAGCCUGGGCAACAGAGUGAGACCCUGCCUGAAAAAAAGCCCAGGUGUGGUGGCUCACAUCUGUAAUCCCAGCAUUUUGGGAUUACAAAUCUGCCAGCGCAAGCAGAUCACUUGAGGAUAGGAGUUUGAGACCAGCCUGACCAACAUGUUGAAACCCCAUCUCUUAUUAAAAUACAAAAAUUAGCUGGGCGUGGUGGCAUGCGCCUGUAAUCCGAGCUACUCAGGUGGCUGAGGCACAAGAAUCGCUUGAACCUGGGAGAUGGAAGUUGCAAUGAGCUGAGAUCAAGCCACUGCACUCCAGCCUGGGCAACAGAGCAAGACUGUCUCAAAAAAAAAAAAUUUGUACAGUCAUGUUCAAAGUAGCAUUAAUUCACAAUAGCCAAAAGCUGGAAGUAGCCCAAGUAUCCACCAAUGAAUGAAAGGAUAAACAAAAUGUGGCAUAUACAUACAAUGGAAUAUUAUACAGCCUUAAAAAGGAAGGAAAUUCAUAUACAUGCUACAGCAUGGAUAAACCUUGAAAAAGUUAUGCUAACUGAAAUCAGCCAGUCACAAAAAGACAAAUACUGUAUGAUUCCCUUUAUAAGAGUUACCUGGAGCACUCAAAUUCAUAGAGACAGUAAAAUGAUGGUUACCAGGGGAUGGGGGAGGGAGAAACAGGAAACUAUUCUUUAGUGAGUACAGAAUUUCAGUUUUUUUGUUUUGUUUUUGUUUUUGUUUUUGAGAUGGAGCCUCACACUGUCACCCAGGCUGGAGUGCAAUGGUGUGAUCUUGGUUCACUGCAACCUCUGCCUCCUAGGUUCAAAUGAUUCUUCUGCCUCAGUCUCCUGAGUCUGGGAUUACAGGCGCCUGCCAUCAUGCCCAGCUAAUUUUUGUAUUUUUAAUAGAGACAGGGUUUCACAGGUUGGCCAAGCUAGUCUCGAACUCCUGACCUCAUGAUCCGCCCACCUCGACCUCCCAAAGUGCUGGGAUUACAGGGGUGAGCCACCAUGCCCAGUCCAGAAUUUCAAGUUUUGCAAGAUGAAAAGAGUUCUGGAGAUGGUUGAUGGUGAUGGUUGCACAACAAUUUGAAUAUUUUAAAUGCCAAUGAACUGUUCAUUUACAAAUGGUUACGAUGGAAUUUUUCUUUUUCUUUUUUUUUUCUUGAGACGGAGUCUCGCUCUGUCACUCAGGCUAGAGUGCAGUGGCACUAUCUCGGCUCACUGCAACCUCCUCCUGCUGGGUUAAAGUGAUUCUCUUGCCUCAGCCUCCCGAGCAGCUGAGACUACAGGCGCGUGCCACCAUGCUCAGCUAAUUUUUUCUAUUUUUAGUGGAGACAGGGUUUCACCAUGUUAGCCAGAUGGUCUCGAUCUCCUGACCUCGUGAUCCACCUCCCUCAGCCUCUCAAAGUGCUGGGAUUACAGGCAUGAGCCACCGUGCACAGCCAAGAUGGAAAUUUUUAUGUUCUUUGUUUGAUAUGGUUUGGCUGUGUCCCCACCCAAAUCUCAACUUGAACUGUAUCUCUCAGAAUUCCCACAUGUUGUGGGAGGGACCCACAGGGAGGUAAUUGAAUCACAAGGGCCGGUUUUUACCAUGCUUUCUUGUGAUAGUGAAUAAGUCUCACAAGAUCUGAUGGGUUUAUCAGGGGUUUCCGAUUUUGCUUCUUCCUCAUUUUCUCUUGCCACUCCCAUGUAAGAAGUGCCUUUCGCCUCCCGCCAAGAUUCUGAGGCUUCCUCAGCCAUGUGGAACUUUGGGGACGAAAAGAGGUUUAAUUGGACUUAAAGUUCCAAUUAAAGUUUCAGGUAUGUCUUUAUCAGCAGCAUGAAAAUGAACUAAUACAGUGUUUUAUCACUUUUUUUUUUUUUUUUUUUUUUUGAGAUGGAGUUUCGCUCUUGUUGCCCAGGCUGGAGUGCAAUGGCGCAACAUCAGGUCACUGCAAACUCUGCCUCCCGGGUUCAAGCGAUUCUCUUGCCUCAGCCUCCUGAGUAGCUGGGAUUACAGGCUUGUGCCACCACACCCGGCUAAUUUUUGUAUUUUUAGUAGAGACAGAGUUUCACCAUGUUGGCCAGGCUAGUCUUGAACUCCUGACCUCAGGUGAUCCACCCACCUUGGCUUCCCAAAGUGGGUGGAUGACCUCUGGGAUUACAGGCGUGCGCCACCGCGCUCGGUCUAUAUUCACCAAUUUUAAGAUGCACAUCUUUCCAUAUUUUAGUAUCUCUAAGUUGGAGUAUGUCUUACAAUUAAUGGCAUCUGACAGUUAUAACUGGCAGCAUUUGUGACUGAAAAACAUCUUAGAUGCAAUGAAAUACAGUGUGUGUGUUUGUAUUGUGCUGCAAUAUAAAAUGUAUUUCAGGCCAGGUAUGGUGGUUCACACCUGUAAUCCCAGCACUUUGGAAGGCCAAAGUGGGAGGAUCACUUGAGCCCAGGAGUUCAAGGCUGCAGUGAGCUCUGAUUAUACCACUGUACUCCAGCCUAGGCAACAGAGCAAGACCCAGUCUCUAAAAAAUAAAUGAAAAUGUUUCUUAUUGUGGAUCACAGUCAAAAGUUUGAAAAAACACAAUCUGUUUGAACAGCACUACUUUCUGACAGGAAAACCCCAACAGGUUAGGAUCUGUGUAUUCCUCAGAGUAAGAAUUUUUCUAAAAAGUUUUUAAAAACUUAAAGUCUUACUGAUCUCUUCCUAUGCUCCAAUUUUAUAGAUAUAACUUAGCCUUGCGAGGUGAUGUAAUUAAAGUCUAACUUCAAGUUGCUGUUGAGCAUAGAUCUCAGGUCUUCUGACUUCACAACACCUUUCUGCCACUUUCAGUGGAUUUUUCCCUCCUAGGGACCAGAGGUCCUCUACUGGAUUAAAAGUUUCUCCAUCCCGGCAGGGUGCGGUGGCUCACGCCUGUAAUCCCAACACUUUGGGAGGCCAAGGCGGGCGGAUCACGAGGUCAGGAAAUAGAGACCAUCCUGGCUAACAUGGUGAAACCCCGUGUCUACUAAAAAUACGAAAAAUUAGCCGGGUGUGGUGGUGCGCGCCUGUAGUCCCAGCUACUCGGGAGGCUGAGGCAGGAGAAUGGCGUGAAGCCAGGAGGCGGAGCUUGCAAUGAGCCGAGAUCGCGCCACUGCACUCUAGCCUGGGCGACAAAGCGAGACUCUGUCUCAAAAAAAAAAAAAAAAAAAAAAAAUUCUCCAUCCCUUUUGAACAAUCUGGAAGUCUGUUUCUCUUAACCUUCAGUUCCCAUUCCAAUCCUUUGUAACCUAUUUCAGGUUAAGCAUUUAUGGAGGUGCCAUGCUUAAUUAGCCAUUAUGGCACUCACUCUAUUUCAAAGGUUAUCCCAGAAUUUGGAGGCUGUAGGGGAAUUCAGAGUGUGAAUUUCACUUGAACAGCACCCUCUGCAGACUUAAAAUAUUCCUCCUAUAUCUGAAGACAAUAAUAAUUUCUUAGAAUUUGCUAGGCUAAACAACUAUUUUUUAGUCCAGUGGCUUGUAAUUAAGUCAUUUUUAGUCUUUAAUUAUGUUGGUUGCUUUUAGAAUUCUCUUUUAGAGUUGGUCUACAUCCUUUUAAAACAUGGGCAAUCCAAAUUUAUAACAGUAAAUUAAGAUACAUAAAAAAAAACACUGGCUAAAUUUAAAAGGAAACACUUCUAGAAUAUACUGUAUUUUGACACAAGACCAGACUGUGCUAUGUGUAUGUGGUGUUUCAAGUAAUUUAAGAAAACUGUUGGAAUUUUCUGUAUUUCCAGUUUCACAAGAAACAACCUCAAGGAGGGCAGUUUAACUGAAAAUUCAGAGGUAUUAUAGCUCUGAAGAAAAAUACUGAUGAGCAGUUAUACAAAAUGAGAAAUUGAGUUCUAAGAAAUGCAUCCCUAACUUCAACAUAAAGAUAGCUAUGAGAAAACAUUCUUUGUACCCAACCAUAAAUGAAUAAAAAUCACCUCAUUUCUCAUCAGAUGUUUACUGGGUUGCUAGUUAUAUAUAGAAUCCUGCAAGAGGCUCAACAGGGAAGUCCAAAGAGUCAAUCAAGAAGGUAUGAUAAUGGCUAAAGAUGGGGACUGUAGGUCAAUGCUCCACGAGGUUCUUCUUUUGUUGCACCAAUAUAGCUGCACUGUUAUACCCAUAUGGUUACAAUCCAGGCCUCAGAAAAUGUUGCAGAUGCCCUCACCAGAAGGCUGAGAACCAGUUCCUCAGUUUGCAUGCCUCCAGACAGCACUAGAAGUCAAACUCAAAUUGCUUACAUGGUAACUUGGUUUAUCCCAACACCAACUAGGAUAUUCCCUCAAUCACAUGAUUGUACUGAAAAUAUAACCAAGUUUUAUUUAUGUUUUUCAUUUGGUAUUAGCCAUCUGGUAUUUAACCUCUGAAAACCACACAAUCUUCUAUACGCUUUUUUCACUGGAAUAAAUGAAACUGCUUACUUUUGA